GCCUACCGCGAAAAACGCGGAAAUGCGGUGGCUGCGGCCCGCGGGCAGGCGUCGGGGUAGGUGUCUGGCCCCGCUCCUGGGCCGACUUCCUCAGCAGCCUUCUAGUGUGGCGGGUUCCCGCCCAGGAAGGGUCUCUGGCUUGAGAUCCCGCAACCCCCGCCUGCGUCCAGGGGCAGCGGGGCCAGCCCCUCCCCUCGCUUCCCGGGCCAGCCUUUGGGGCCUACCGCAGCUGCAGUAGUCUGGACGCGCAGGGGUCGCGGGGUCGCAGGGUCACCAGUCCCGGCGAGGGAGGUGGAGCCCUGCGGAGCUGGCGGGCGCAGAGUCCUGGUGCGGGAGGUGCCCGCUCAGAAGGCCCGGACUCUAGCUGAGGCUCUUCUCCGACACCUUCCUGCCCCUUUUGGACCCAGUGCCAGGCCAUGCACACAGUGAAGCUGGCUGGAAGCCGCUCCUUCACCCCCUACCCUACUGUCCCGCCCAGGGCCCCGCAGCCUCGCGGUCAGCUGUGUGGGCCAUUGAUUGUUCUGCCCAGCUCAGAAAGAGUUGUGGGCGUGGGCCUCCUGCCCGCCUGUCUCCUGUGCUCCCCCAGGGAGCCCUUACAUAGCCGAAAGUUGCAGAGAUGAAGGGUGAAAGCUGGAAUGAUUGGGUUUUAAUGGGUCAGGUCUGGGACCUGGCUUUUCUCCUGGAGCAGAGGGAAUACUUGUCAUGGUAAUGGGGUAGCCCAGAGGGUGUGGACACGGCUGGGAAAAGUGAGGCUUCAGUUUGGGGGUCAGGUAGGUGAGUGCCUGUCACUGAGGUCAAAGGAGCUGUGGGCUGGGCCUGGCGGUGGAGGCGGGUGCCUGUAGUUUCAGCAAGUCAGGAGGCGGAAGUGGGAGGAUCACCUGAGCCCAGGAAUUCGAGGUUAACGUGCGCUGUCAUCACACCGAAGCAUUCCAGCCUGGACAGCGGAGCAAGACCCUGUCUCUAAAGAAUUAAUUAUUAAUUUAAAAACAGGCUGUGGGCAGGAGUGUACUAUUGCCAGUUAGCGUUCAGCACAGUCCCCAGCUUGUCACUGUUACCUGUCUGCUUCCCCCACACACCCAUGGCUAUGCUGGGCUGGCUCACAGGCAGCAGUGCCCCCCUAUUUAUCCCGCUGCUGCUGCCAGGCUAGGUAGGGGAUGCUGGGGCCUCCCUCAGGGUGUUGGUCACUAAGUGGUCCCCCCGCUAAGCUGAGCAGUGGCUCAGCCUCUCACACCUCCUCCAGGCUGGGCUGGCCCAGAACUCACCUAGGGGCCUGGUCUGGGGUCUCCCUGGAGGCUCCUGGUAACAAACAGCCCCACCCCUUCUGGGUGCUGGUAUCCAUGGCAACGGUAUACAGCCCUUCCCUCCCAGGCCUGCUUGGAGGUCGGGCCUCAGAGCAAGAGUCGGUCAGUGGUCACCUGGGACCUCCAGCAGGCGCACCUGCAGCCCCCGAGACUCCCACGUGCCUGCCAGACACCACGCCCCACCCCGCACCGGUGGUCUGCUCUGCCGACCCGCAGUUGGCUCUUGAGUCCCUGGACCCUCGCACACUGCGGCUGCUGUGGAGACAGCGAGAACUGGAGAUCCAGGCCUUGCGGUGGGCCAUCCAGAAUGGCGAGGACGCCCGGCUCUGCCACAUCCUGGAAGAGGUGGCGGGGCUUCCGCCCAAGAGGAGCUCCCACAGUCAGGAGAAACUCCUGCAGAACCAGGUCCAGAAGCUGAUCCAGGAGUUGAAGGAACAGAAGGAGCGAGCCCAGUGGGCCCUCUCGGAGCAGGAGAAGGAGCACCUGGAGGAGCGGCUGCUGCAGACCACCCGCACGCUCCAGGAGAUGGAGGCCGAGCUGCAGAACUUGCAGAAGUCCUGCCUCCUGCAGCUGGCCCGCUCCUCGUGGGUGGGCCGCAUGCUACGAUCCCAGACUGGCAGUGUGGAGGUAGUGACGGCAGAGACUCUGAUGGACCCAAGCGACCUCUCUGAAAACAUUCAGGCCCCCACCGGGGAGGGCUUUCGGCUGGAGGACGUGGAUUGGAACAGCGUUGCCCGCCGGUAUCCCAACCUCUUCACCAACAUGGAGCCCAGCUCAAAGCAAAAGCAGCCCCGGCCCUGGCCACAGCUGGACACAGGGAGCCCAGAGUCCUCUGGAAAGCAUUCCGAGCGGCAUCACAAGACCGUGGAGUGGGGCUCCCUGCCCUGUCUGAACACCAGCAGCUCAGGGGGCGCUGACUCCGACUCCAGCAGCUGCCGGCCGGGCCUGCCUUCCUUCGUGCAGGUGAUAGGGCACCCGCCCCGGGACCACCGCGCUUCCUCCGAGCAAGCGCUGGUGCAGGCCGGCAGCUACAGCAGGGACUCAGAAGAUCUCCAGAAAACCCACUCACCCAGGCACGGCGAGCCGGUCCUGUCGCCCCAGCCCUGCACAGACCCGGACCACUGGAGCCCGGAACUCCUGCAGAGCCCGACAGGCCUGAAGAUCGUGGCUGUGAGCUGCCGGGAGAAGUUCGUCCGCAUCUUCAACCCGUCGCAGGAGAGCACGGCCGACCUGAGCGGCAUGGUGCUGAAGCAGCUGGUGCGCGGCUUCCCGGAGCGCCUGUACCGCUUCCCGCCGGGCACGCUGCUGGCCCCGCGGCACCACGUCACGGUCUGGGGCGAGGCGACCCGCAGCGCCAAGAAGCCGCUGCGCGCGUCCUCGAGCCGGGAGCCCGUUCCCCUCCUCUCCAUCCGCGGCUGCGCGACGCUGCUCCUGAGCCCCAAGGGCGAGGUCCUCAGUGAGCACCGGAUCCCACGCCGCGAGACUCCGGCCCCGAGGGUCUUCGCCGACGGCACCGACUUGUCCAUCGACCGCUUCCCGCUCCCUGAGGCCGGGCCCGGCGCCGACACCCGCAAGCCGCCGCGCCCACCUCGACCCCUGCGCAAAGGCCGGGUGCGGGAGCCCCGGGUCAGUCGCCGGAGACCAGGGACGCGGGGCCUGCUGCCCCCAGUGAGCUCGGGGAAGCUCUUCCACGCGCGGGAGGGGCCUGCGCGGCCCGAGAACCCCGAGAUCCCCGCGCCGCAGCACCUGCCCGCCAUCCCGGGUGACCCCACCCUGCCGUCGCCUCCCGCAGAGGCCGGGCUGGGCCUGGAGGACUGUCGGCUCCAGAAAGAACACCGAGUUCGGGUGUGCCGGAAGAGCGUGGACCGUAGCUGCCCCCUGGUGGCCCUGUCGGUGCAGAACACGGCGGAGAGCAGAUUCGGCUUCCGCUUCCUCAGCUGCCUGCCGGUCACCGCGGACACCUGCCGCGGCGCCUAGGGGCGGAGGAGUGGGGCCGGGACCGCGAGGGAGGGCGCGGGCGGGCGCCGGGGCUGGGCGGGCUGUGUCCGCUGCAUCAUUUAUUGAACCAACGUGGCCUACAAAGUAAACCGCAUUUCUGUACACCUGA